AGAUCCUUCAAAUGGAUCCUUUCUGAAUGCAAAACUGUACAUCUCUAACUGGAUUCUUAUUUACUUCACCAGGACUCUUCAGCUCCCUGCGCCUUUUAACACAUGCACAUCCAGCAAAAGCAGAGGAGAACCUGGCUGUGAUUCAAAGUGUGUGAACCCAGCUCUGUCCCUUGGGUUCCGUACAUAUAAAUGGAGCAGCUGAGGGAACUGGAUAAGAAGUCGAUUUUGUAGUUACAGGCUGUUCCGUAUCACCCAUUUACAAGAGUCUCACUCUACUGCCCAGGCUGGAGUGCAGUGGUACAAUCUUGGCUCACUGCAGCCUCCGCCUUCCGGGUUCCAGUGAUCCUCCUGCCUCAGCCUCCCAAGUAGCUGAGAUUACAGCGUGAGUGCAUCUCCAUCCACGUUGGCCAGGCUGGUGUCCAGAUUGGCAAUGCCUGCUGGGAGCUCUACUGCCUGGAACACGGCAUCCAGCCCGAUGGCCAGAUGCCAAGUGACAAGACCAUUGGGGGAGGAGAUGAUUCCUUCAACACCUUCUUCAGUGAAACGGGUGCUGGCAAGCAUGUGCCCCGGGCAGUGUUUGUAGACUUGGAACCCACAGUCAUUGAUGAAGUUCGCACUGGCACUUACCGCCAGCUCUUCCACCCUGAGCAACUCAUCACAGGCAAGGAAGAUGCUGCCAAUAACUAUGCCCGAGGGCACUACACCAUUGGCAAGGAGAUCAUUGACCUCGUGUUGGACCGAAUUCGCAAGCUGGCUGACCAGUGCACCGGUCUUCAGGGCUUCUUGGUUUUCCACAGCUUUGGUGGGGGAACUGGUUCUGGGUUCACCUCGCUGCUCAUGGAACGUCUCUCAGUUGAUUAUGGCAAGAAGUCCAAGCUGGAGUUCUCCAUUUACCCGGCGCCCCAGGUUUCCACAGCUGUAGUUGAGCCCUACAACUCCAUCCUCACCACCCACACCACCCUGGAGCACUCUGAUUGUGCCUUCAUGGUAGACAAUGAGGCCAUCUAUGACAUCUGUCGUAGAAACCUCGAUAUCGAGCGCCCAACCUACACUAACCUUAACCGCCUUAUUAGCCAGAUUGUGUCCUCCAUCACUGCUUCCCUGAGAUUUGAUGGAGCCCUGAAUGUUGACCUGACAGAAUUCCAGACCAACCUGGUGCCCUACCCCCGCAUCCACUUCCCUCUGGCCACAUAUGCCCCUGUCAUCUCUGCUGAGAAAGCCUACCACGAACAGCUUACUGUAGCAGAGAUCACCAAUGCUUGCUUUGAGCCAGCCAACCAGAUGGUGAAAUGUGACCCUCGCCAUGGUAAAUACAUGGCUUGCUGCCUGUUAUACCGUGGUGACGUGGUUCCCAAAGAUGUCAAUGCUGCCAUUGCCACCAUCAAAACCAAGCGUACCAUCCAGUUUGUGGAUUGGUGCCCCACUGGCUUCAAGGUUGGCAUUAAUUACCAGCCUCCCACUGUGGUGCCUGGCGGAGACCUGGCCAAGGUACAGAGAGCUGUGUGCAUGCUGAGCAAUACCACAGCUGUUGCCGAGGCCUGGGCUCGCCUGGACCACAAGUUUGACCUGAUGUAUGCCAAGCGUGCCUUUGUUCACUGGUACGUGGGUGAGGGGAUGGAGGAAGGCGAGUUUUCAGAGGCCCGUGAGGACAUGGCUGCCCUUGAGAAGGAUUAUGAGGAGGUUGGAGCAGAUAGUGCUGACGGAGAGGAUGAGGGUGAAGAGUAUUAACCUGUGUGCUGUACUUUUACACUCCUUUGUCUUGGAACUGUCUUAUUUUUGUUCUGUAAAUGUCUAUUGCCGUAAAUUGUUAAUAAAAUUGAAGUUUCCAUUUUAAAUGUCGAGCUGACUUAAAUACUUGAUCCAGUUAAAGUUGGAUGUAUGAGGCUGGUAGAUGAAACCACCUGAGUCGAGGGUCUUGCUCUGUCACCCAGGCUGGAGUGCAGUGGCAUGAUAAUACAUAGCUCAUUGCAGCCUCGAGCUCCUGGACUCAUGUGAUUCUCCUGCUUCAGCCUCCUAAGUAGCUGGGGACUGCAGGUGCACACCACCAUGCCCAGCUAUUUUUAUUUCUUGUAGAGAUGGGGCCUUGCUAUGCUGCCCAGGGUGGUCUUCAACUGGCUUCAAGUGAUCCUCCUGCCUCAACCUCUCAAAGUUUUGAUUAUAGGCAUGAGCCACUGCCCAGCUUCUUGGUUUAUCUGUUUAAUUUGGGCCUGAAUUAAGUGGUUAUAGAAUCAUUUUGUAAGUGAGGAAACGGGUUCAGAUUGAGCCAGUGCUUCUCUAACUAAAAUGGAUGUGAAUCACCUGUAGAUAUUAAAAUGCAGGUUUGGGGUCAACCUGGUGGCUCAUGCACUUCGGGAGGCCAAGUUGGGUGGAUCACGAGCCCAGGAAUUCGAGACCAGCCUGGGCAACAUGGUGAAAACCCAUCUCUACCAAAACAAAAAUUUGCAUGCUGUGAUGGCACCUGCCUAUAGGUGGGAGGACCACCUGAGCCCAAGGAGGUUGAGGUAGUGAGCCAUGAUUGCACCACUGCAUUCCAGCCUGGGUGACGGAGACCCCUGACUCUCAAAUUUAAAAACAAAAUGCAGGUUCUAAUUCUAUAGGCUUGAGGUGAGGCUUCAGACACGUCUUAAAUUUUUUUUCUUUGAGAUGGUCUCUUUCCCAGGCUGCAGUGCAAUGGCACCAUCAUAGCUCACCCCCACCUUGACCUGGGCUAAGCCAUCCUCCCACCUCAGCCUCCCAAGUAGCCAGGACUACAGGUGUGUUCCACCAUGCCUGGCUGAUUCUUGUAAUUUUUUUUUUUUUUUUUUUUUUUUUUUUUGGUAGAGAUGGGGUUUUGCCAUGUUGCUUAGGCUGGCCUUGAACUCCUGGGCUCAGGCAAUCCUGCCUCAGCCUCCCAAAGUGCUGGGAUUACAGGAGUGAGCCACUACACCUGGCCCCUAGAUACGUUUUUUAAUAACCUCCCAAAUGAUGCUGUUGGUCUGAUGUGACCACAUGUACAGUAGCAAAGGGUUAGAUAACAGUAACUGCUGGAGCCAAAAUUCAAGUGCCCAGCCACACUGCCAGAACUAUUGCUGUCAGUCUUUAAUAAAGUAUUAGUCACACGA